UAAGUUUACAAUUGCCCAAACACAAGGUCAGGAAUGAAGUUAAAUAUGUCAGCAUGGUACUGCCUUCUUGUCUUAUUUCUCCUUUCCCCUAUCACUUUGACCUCUUGUGCCUUCCGAAGUGAAUGAGGUAACACUUCAUAUGCUGAUUGCCUGUGAAAAGGGCAUCUUUAUUCAUUGAGACAAUCCUUCUAGGCUUAAAAUCAACCCAAAAUCAAGGAAAAGGGGUCUCAUGAUUCCUUCAGCUUCUACAUUGAUGAAGCCUCUCCAGUAGGUCCUGAGCAGCCAGAAACUGUCCAGAAUUUUGUCUCUGUGUUUGGAACUGUGGCCAAAAAGCUCAUGCGGAAAUGGUUAGCCACUCAGACAAUGAAUUUUACUGGCCAGCUAGGAGCUGGAAUUCGUUAUUUUGAUCUUCGAAUUUCCACCAAGCCCAGAGACCCCGACAAUGAACUCUAUUUUGCUCAUGGUUUGUUCAGUGCCAAAGUCAAUGAAGGCCUUGAGGAGAUCAAUGCAUUCCUCACAGAUCACCAUAAGGAGGUAGUGUUCUUGGACUUCAACCACUUUUAUGGGAUGCAGAAAUAUCACCAUGAAAAACUGGUCCAAAUGCUGAAAGACAUCUAUGGAAAUAAAAUGUGCCCAGCGAUUUUUGCCCAGGAAGUUAGUUUAAAGUACCUGUGGGAGAAGGACUAUCAAGUGCUGGUCUUCUACCAUAGUCCAGUGGCUCUGGAAGUGCCCUUUCUCUGGCCUGGGCAGAUGAUGCCAGCACCCUGGGCCAACACCACAGACCCCGAGAAACUGAUCCAGUUUCUUCAAGCAUCCAUCACUGAGAGAAGAAAGAAGGGAUCGUUUUUUAUAUCUCAGGUGGUGCUGACCCCCAAAGCUAGCACUGUGGUCAAAGGGGUGGCAAGUGGCCUCAGAGAAACAAUCACAGAAAGAGCUCUUCCUGCCAUGAUGCAGUGGGUCCGCACGCAGAAGCCAGGAGAGAGUGGCAUCAAUAUUGUCACUGCCGAUUUUGUAGAACUUGGUGACUUUAUCAGCACUGUCAUAAAGCUCAACUAUGUCUUUGAUGAAGGAGAAGCCAACACUUGAUAGCACUACUUGGAGUUUCCAUGAAUAAGAUGGAGAAAGCUCAUUGUAUUAGGGCAUACUAUCUGUAAACACUCUGAUCUUCCUAUUCCACUGAGUCUCUGAAGGGAAUAGGGCUGGUAGUGGGUGGGAAAAGGGGAAAAACUGUUUCUUCAGUGAUUACAAUCAUACUCUUCAUUACUAUAAAUAUUUCAUUUCCCAUUUGAUGAGCAAAAUCUACUUCUAGUGUUAGGAAUAAAAAAAAAAGACCAGUAACUUUGUUUUUCAAAAUUAGUCUUUGUAACAUAGAAUUCAUGAGUGUUUACUUGAUUAGGUUCUCUAUUUCCAGCCUAUGACUCCUACGCUGUCUAUACCCUGCAACCUUUCUGCUCCCUCUCUUGCUCGCUCUUUUUAAUCAGAUGCUGUAUGGGAAUCAAAACAAUUGAAUGCCCAACAUUUUGUGUAUUACAUUGUUGUCUUAAAACUUACUAGUUUUGUGGGACUUGUUAUAAUGCUCUAUAGUCAUCCACAGUUGGGCAAUCAUAGCUAAUUUUUGGUCAUAGAAAAUCUGCAUCAAAUCAGUUUCCAUGCAUCAGUAAUAUUGAAGGUCAUAAUCAGUGAUUUUUGUUAUAUGAAAAUAAUAGUGUUUCACAGUAUUUCUAUUUAAGGCAGCUAUAAAUAUAGGAGAAAAAUGUUUUUGGAGAGCUGUGAAUGCCAAUUUCAGAGGGAAAAAUGGUUGAGGGGUGAAAGAGAUGUAUGGCAUUUUAAUUUGGCAAUCUCUUAAAUAAUAUUGCCCUGCAAGUACCCAGUAAAUGGUAAGGUACAAGUGUGUUAAAAUUGAAAACUCUGAAAAUAACUCUUUAAAAAGCCCUCUUAAUGAUGCUCUUGAUGAAAGAAAAAGACAGAAGGAAGGAAGGAAGGAAGGAAGGAAGGAAGGAAGGAAGGAAGGAAGGAAAGGAAGAAAGGAAGGGAGGGAGGAAGGGAGGGAAGAAGGGAGGGAAGGACAGAAGGAAGGACGGGAGGAAGGAAGGAAGGGAGGAAGGAAGGAAGGAAGAGAGGGAGGGAGGGAGGAAGAGAGGGAGGGAGGGAGGAAGAGAGGAAGGAAGAAGAAAAAGACUGCAAGCUUUCCUGCCAAUUUGGGAUUUUCAAAUAUUUAAUUCUAAAUUCCAGAUUUUAAGGAAGAUUUUUCAAGAAACUGCAAGUUUUUGACUUGAAGGAAAGAAAGAGGAAGGCUGGUAGAAGCAGUUAGAGCAAUGUGUUUGAAAUUAUGUCCAUGAAAUCACAGGGAUCUCUGAAAUAUCUUUAGGAAACUUGAAAUUUAUGAGGUCUGAAUGGACUUGUUUAAAAUUGGCUCUGACUCCUCACUUCUGAGUUUCAUCCUAUCCGAGGGAUGAGAUUAAGGCAGAGGCAAAAGUUUCACACAAAGUUUCUGCAACCUAACGUUUAAUAGUCCGGGUCUACAGGGAAGAACAAUGACACAGCUUGAGCGUUACUUCCUCCUUCGUGUCAUUGUGAUAUUUGACAACUCUAAAAAAUAAAAAAAAAAAACUUAGAGCACAAUAAUCCUUGCCUAUGUACUUCACAGGAAUAUUGUGAGGUGUUUAUAAAAUUAUAAAAUUUGAUGAAAUUCUUACAAUUAUUAAUUAUUUUAUUUUCAUGUUUAGAAAUAAUCACACCCCAAUAGUUUCCUAGGAUAAUACAGUCCAUGCAAAGUAGGGUCAUAGAGAAAUAAAAGCAUGCCCUCAGCUUUUAAUGAACUUAAAUGUAGCACAUAUGGCUUAAUCUCUUAGACUUAGAUAAGGGAGUUCAAUUCAAAACCAUAUAUGUCAAGACCACAAAUAAUCAAGAGUUGAUUUCAAGAUUAUAAAUACUCAUGAUCAGAAAAUAGUACUUAUUAGCAAUUAAAGGGAGGAAAAGAAAUUGUUUAUACUGAAGAGAAUGUUUAUGAGGAGUGUGUAUGUACCUGUGGUAUACCAAAUAGCAUACAUGUACACACAAAAAUGUGUGUAUACAUUUGGGUUGUGUGUAUACAUCUUGCCAUAUACAAUAUACAAACAUAUGCCCAUUCCUGUGAUAGCAUACAAAUUCAAACAUACAGAAACACACACAGAUAUGGACACAGUACAAUUCUUCUUUUCAAAUGAAGACAUUGAUAAUAUUAAAUAAUUUAAUUUUAAGACUGAAACCCUUAAUAUUGUGUGAAAAAGAGUAAUAAAACCUUUGAAAGUAGAGUAGAUGAUCACAUCAAAGUAUUUUUGUAAAAGAAUUCUAGUGUAGGACUUAAUUAUUUUUAAAAUAUAUUUCUUCUCUUCUUUCCAUUUUCCCUUCCCUUGUAGUUUUAUUAUCUUUCUGUCUUUUACACCUGCUCUUUAUGUGAAAAUGUAUAUGAAUCCUUUUAAAAUGAUUAGGAUUAUUGAAAUGUAUGUCCCGUAAAUUUGGUUUUUGGGCAGACUUUCUCUCUAACUGGCUAUUCAUUCAUCCUUCAGGAGGAUCUUAGCCAAGAAUAUUUGCAAUGACACAUGAAUUUAAUUUUAUAAAUAUAAUGGAAAACAGAUUUUUCAUCAUAUCAUGAAUAAAAUAUAGAGGUAACUAUGUUGUAUUUUCUUGAACCUAGAUACUUUCUCAUAGUGUUUGCUUAGAAUUAACUUUGUCCUAUUUGUCAACUGGGUUCUGGAAAAAAACAAACAUGAUGAAGCUUUUGAAUAAUUGUGCAGUUUUUUAACUAGGGAAAGCUUUGUACUGCUGCUAAUGAUAUGCACCCAGAAACCUUGUUAGACAAAAGGCAGUUUCAAGCCAAUGCUAUGGUUUCCAUGUGGACAUACAGUGCCUAUGUAGCAGGCACUUAGAGUAAAUGGACUUGCCUUAAUUUAUAAAGGAGGGAAGAGGUAGAAGGGAACCAUGGGUCCUCCAGCUAGAGGGGGAGUUUACUAAAAGGGAGUCCUUGGAAAGGGGAAUGGAGAGAAGGUGCCUUUGACUGUCUUCUAUCCAUUAGUUCUGCCCUGGAGCACACUGGGGAAGCAGGCUGCGGGCCUUCCAAAAGUAAAAAAUGGUGAUAUGCAAUCGAAGCUUAUCCUUAGCCUAUGCACAUUUGUCUCAGCUGGGCAUUGUCUUUUCAGAGAGCUUGUAGCACAAGGGCUACACAUGGGCGCCAAGAUGGUGGUAGAUACACCUUGGUGCACUUUUUGUUUUACUUGUUUCUUAAGACUAUUUCACAAGUCCUGUGAGGCAAAAAAACAAAACAAAACAAAACAACCAAACAAAUACAAUCUAACUUUUACCCAAUCUACAGCAGGAAAUCAAAGGAGUGGGUGGAAUGAGAGAAAAUAUGCAAAGAGAUCAUUUUUAAGUUUGAUUUCCUGUCUGUAAUUUUCAAGGACUAAUAUAGCAAAUUUUUCUUCUGCCAUUAUCAUUUAUGUCUCCCUAUUUACCACACAAUAAUGUAAAUGCAGAGAAUGAGGAGGCAUCUUUUAAAAGCCUUAGGAUAUUCUAUAUGAUGACCUCAAUAUUGACUUUCAGCCAUACUGGGAAAACUUACUUUUCAUGGAGUGCCACCUAACAGUGAAUGUAUUAGAGUAUAAAAUGUUUGCCAUGUAUACACCUGUAUGUGCACAUACACACAUUACACACACACACAGAAUGCACAUUUCACACACAUAUACUUAUUAUUCAAGUUGAAACUGCACUCUAAUCAAUCUGAGUCUAUUGCUGUUUCAACUCUUAAAAUCAAUAUCUCCUACAUUAGUAGAUAUAAACAUAAUUCAAAUAUUUAAAUAUUUAAGAGGAGAAAAGUAACUAGAAAACCAAUGAAAAGUGAGGCCAUCAGAAAUAGAAAAUGCCUGGCACGAACAGUCUAUCUAAAUUCUCAAUUUCACUUCAAAUUAGAGAAUCCAUAAUGGACUAGAAUAUAAAUUACAAACACAUACACACAUCUUCACUUAAAGUUGUUUUAAGUUCUUUGAAGUUCUGACAUGUUUUUAGCCAGGGUUAUUUGUUCAGGUUCUUCCUUGUUAGGAUUCCAGACUGGAAAGUUGGAAGUCUCAGGAAAUGCAUGUUUCCAUGAGUUUUUUAGUUUCACAGUUUUACAGAUCCAACGACACAAUCUUUUAAUCUUUGGUCACUCAACCAAACAGGAGUUCCGUAGGCAGAGUGCUCACUUUGAAUUGCUAAUAGAAAAUAAUGCACAGUGUCCUCAGGAUAUGCUAAACAAGGUUUUUAAGAGCAUUUUAUUUUACAGCACUUUAGUCUUUUCAGCUAGAUUUCAGUGACACUAUGGUGUAAAUGCUAUAUCUGCCAUAACUUAUUGGUGGCUCCUGUGUUACAUACAGUUUUAAAUAAUGCUCUAAAUUGUUUGUUUUCCCAAUGAUAAUGAUAAAGUGUUCUGUAGAAUUUGUAAAACAUGUCAAUUGAAUCUGUUGAAAAUUGUGUAAUUGUUAUUUCAAUUGUGAUACUAUUUUGUAGGUAAUAGUUUUAAACGUAUAUUUGUAUGAGUCAAAAGUAUGUGCUUGUAUGUGGUAUGUGUGUGUAAGUAUAUAAUAUCUUAUCAAAAAUCAAACUUAUCCUAAAGAAAAAGGGCACAUUGUGACCAGCCUUAAUUUAUUAACACUUUUUUGUUGUUUUUGCAAUUUGGAUUUAAAAUUGAAACAGAAAUUAAGUUUUUGUUAAAAAUGGUGUCUUUUAAUUUUGUGAGGAAUGGGCUUUAGAACCUAUCUGAGUUCCCACAAGCAAACUGUCCACCUUGUGAGGUACCCCAUUGCUUUUCGUAAUAAUCAAACAUCAAUUCAUAUAUUAACUUCAUUUUCAUACAGACUAAUUUGUUUUCAUCAACAAUAGAACCAGUACACCUUUAAAGUUGACCUUCCCAACAUGGCACCCAUUUUUCUUUAAUGAUAAAUUUUCCAUGAAAAAUUGUUUCUCCAAACCAUUACUUUUUAAAAUUCAAUCUUCCCAAGUAAGAUGAACUGCCUUGGUGUUAGGAGAGCUUUUAAAGGCCCAUCCAUACUAGGUGGUUCCAACAUGGUUCUCUUCUCGAGAAAACAAGCAUGCAACCCACACACUUUUCUGGUCUGCCCCACGUGUAGAAUUAGUCUAGCAAUAGAAAACUCAUGACUGACAAGGAUCUACACAUGUGGUCAUGCUUGAAGCAAAAAUUCUGUGACCUUCUUUGGGCUUGGAUCUGAUUACAGAAUAUUAAUUAACUUUCUUAUUUCCUUUCUUUCUCCAUCCUUAGUUAUUCCUUUUCAAUAUUUAGAGUUGCCAGGUAAAAUACAGGAUAUCCAGUGAAAUUUAAAUUUCAGAUAAACAGUAUUUCUUUAGCAUAUUUCUCAUAUAUUUAAUCAGACAUACUUUCACUUUAAAAAAAGUUUAUCUGAAAUUCAAAUGUAACUGGGUAUGUCCUAUAUAUUUUUUCCUAAAUCUCACAAUUCUAUCCACACUGCCUUUCUAUCUUUUUCAGCUGGGCUAUCUAUAAGGGGCGAGAUCUACCUCCCUCCAUACCCUUGUGUUCAGACACCUUAUGAAUAUCUGCAGUCAUAAUGUCCUUCAAGAAAGAAAACAUUGGUCAGCUCUAGGUCCUGCAAAUGCUUUUUGAAGGACGAACUCAAAUACAGAUGGGAUAAUCAAGUAAAUAUCUUCAUAGGAUCAAUGCCACCAUGUUCAACACUUCCCUUUGCCAGCCUGUUGUGAGGUCCAAGUUUCCCCAUUAAUCCCUUAUAUAGCAUUUCCCAGUAACUGGGACAACCAAAAACACACCGACAUAUUAGAAAUGCUCCUGAAAAGUGGCAACACCGCCUAACUCAGUACCAGGACCUCUUUUAAAUUCAAUUUCUUUUUUCUUUCAGAGAGAUAACAAACGAAUUCAUUAUUUCCCCCAUUCACAUCUUACCACAAAUUAUUUUUAUCAGGUUAAAACUGGUCAUCUACGGAAUUGUAGAAAGGUGACAUAGGAACUGUCUUCACUGCUGGAAGAAUAAAAGAGUCUGAGGUAUAGACACUGCCCUGGUGACACCUUCUCAGAACAUUGUUGGGGGACAGGGGAGGCAGGCGCAAGUAGGGGAUAGAAUCUGACCCUGACAUGCAGCUAUCACCUGGCAGAGAGACUCGUCAAAGCAAAUUAUAACGACCAGUACUAUUUUUUUUUGGAAUUGAAAACCCAAGAAGCCCUAAAAUAAGAACAGUGAGAUCAAAGGCUGGUUUCUAAAACAAUGCAGAAAAUAGAACCAUGUUGGAAUUCCUAAAUUCUAGCUUUCAAAUACUACUGUUUCCAACAGUGAAUCCUUGACAGAGACUGAAUGCAGAUGGAAUUUUGAAACAUUUUCAGUAGCUACCUCCUCUCCUGAAAUUCCUAUAAGUGGCAGAGGAAAAUCCAAAUCCUUUAAUAUAACAUGUCCAUCUCAUGACUCCUGCUUACACACAUUUGUGUUGAUUUGCUUCAUUUCUGGAGGAUGGGAAUUUGCAGAGCUGGUGACAUUUCCUUCAUUAGACACCAGAAAUUCACCAGAGAGAGACAGAUCUGUGCCUUCUCUUUUUAGGAUCUGGUUAUUGAUACUUUAAUAAAUGUGGUGUAAAGAAAAUCCAUGGCUACAGUCUGUAUAGAAAAUGUGAAUUUUUUAAAUAAGAUUGUGUUCUUAAUGUAAAAAAUAAAAGUUUAUUUGUAUUCAGUGAAAUGCCUAAUAAAGUCCUGGUACCAAUUA